GGGUGUCGUCCUCAACCACCUUCGCUGCCUUCUUGGGCAGGUUGGUGUCGGUUUAGUUUCUGCGGUUUGCAGGGUUGACAUCCUAACUCCUUUGAGUUUCGCAUCCCCCUUUUGUGGAGGGGGCUCAGAGCCUGGAGAAGCAACAGACGGGGAAUUAAGGCAGAUGCAGCCCAGCACAGCGUGGAGGGGUCCGAAGUGGCCUCACGGGGGCCUGAGCAUGGCUGUCUUUCCAGGCUCCUCUUUAUUUGCCAGGAGCCCAGCUAAGCCCAACUUUACUCCCAGAAAUGUUGAGGGGAAUCUGCGGACUCGAGGCCCCUCGCCUCGGGACCAGCGGCUUCUCUUCGCCGCAGCUCACGCAUGAUCGGGGUGGGAUUCCGUCUUCCUUCCGGGAGAGGAGAAUGCCCAGCUGCCUGGGAUGGGGAAACGUUGCCGGAUCUCUGGGGAAUGUGGUCUCAAGGCUGCAGGGGCCUGGCAGAGAGGAACUGUCCAUCACUAGGACAUAGCCGAAGCUCGCCUUAGCGAAGAGAGUCUCACCUCCUCGGGCUUUGCACAGAGUUGGAGAAGAGGUCGGGAAUCACAGGGAGGCUGGAUUUUGGCUGCUCUGUCCCCAGCCUGCAGGUCCCUGUUCGCCCUGUGGCUCGGAAUUUUAUUACUGAUGUAUAUAAUCUGAUAAUCUUUUCUUAAUGAUGCCUAACAAGUGUGAUUUUUUUCCCCCUUGGGUUUGUAAGACAGUUGAUUUUAUGUGAGGAGAUUGAUCCAGUUCUUAUAUUUUAGCCAGUGCUUGUCUAACAGAGAUUGGGAGAGCUAUCCCGUGCUGGGCUGUUGCACAGUUUUCAUCUCCAUUCACUGAGAUGCUUCAGUAAUGAAUUUAUUGUUUUAUGGCUUUUUGGAGAUGGUGGUGGUGGUGGUGUGAUUAUAACCCUGCUGGAAAAUCUUAUUACUGUUAUCUGAAUUGAAGAGACAGAAAGGAUGCUGAGCCCCCUAGGGAUUCCGUAGGGGAAUGAUGUAGUGUCCCGCCCACCAGUAGUGAACCUGACAGUGAAAUUCUCUCUCCAGUCUGCUAGUUUUCAAAGCAUGUUCUAGGCAGGUACACGUACUAUCACCUAGGCUUUAAAAGUGAAGAAGCAGAUUUGGAGGUUAAGAACAACUGGGCCUUGGAAUUAAUAGAAUGCAGUGGACAACUUUUGCCUCUCCUUCCUCCACCCCCUCCCUCCCUUCCUUCUUUCCUUUUUUUUCAUCCUUUAAAAAUAAAAAUAAGGGCCAGGCAUGGUGCUUAUGCCUGUAAUCCCAGCACUUUGGGAGGCCGAGGCAGGCGGAUCAUGAGGUCAGGAGAUCGAGACCAUCCUGGCCAACACAGUGAAACCCCGUCUCUACUAAAAAUACAAAAAAUAAAAAUUAGCUGGGCGUGGUGGCACGCACUUGUAAUCCCAGCUACUUGAGAGGCUGAGGCAGGAGAAUCGCUUGAACCCGGGAGGUGGAGGUUGCAGUGAGCUGGGAUUGCGCCACUGCACUCCAACCUGGCGACAGAGCAAGACUCUGUCUCAAAUAAAUAAAUAAAUAAAUAAGUAUGAAAUAUUUCUAACAUACAUAAAAACAGAGUAUAGUAAGCCAUUUUGUCUUCUACUUCCUAGGUUUAAUAGUUGCUAAUAUUUUCAUAUUUGAUCCAUACCUCUCCCCCCCCGGAAAAAUAAACUAUAACUUAAAUAUUUGAUCUAUUCCUACUCCUUUGCCUCCAUCCUCAGGUAACCUCUAAUGUGAAGUUAGCGCACACAGUUCUCAAGCAUGUUUGGAACUACACUGUAUCCACAAAAAAAUACAUGUGUUGAAAAGUCUCCUCUAGAGCUUUGGAAGGCUGAAUGCACUAAACAUGAAGAGCUUGAAAGCGAAGUUCAGGAAGAGUGACACCAAUGAGUGGAACAAGAAUGAUGACCGGCUACUGCAGGCCGUGGAGAAUGGAGAUGCGGAGAAGGUGGCCUCACUGCUCGGCAAGAAGGGGGCCAGUGCCACCAAACACGACAGUGAGGGCAAGACCGCUUUCCAUCUUGCUGCUGCAAAAGGACACGUGGAAUGCCUCAGGGUCAUGAUUACACAUGGUGUGGAUGUGACAGCCCAAGAUACUACCGGACACAGCGCCUUACAUCUCGCAGCCAAGAACAGCCACCAUGAAUGCAUCAGGAAGCUGCUUCAGUCUAAAUGCCCAGCCGAAAGUGUCGACAGCUCUGGGAAAACAGCUUUACAUUAUGCAGCGGCUCAGGGCUGCCUUCAAGCUGUGCAGAUUCUCUGCGAACACAAGAGCCCCAUAAACCUCAAAGAUUUGGAUGGGAAUAUACCGCUGCUUCUUGCUGUACAAAAUGGUCACAGUGAGAUCUGUCACUUUCUCCUGGAUCAUGGAGCAGAUGUCAAUUCCAGGAACAAAAGUGGAAGAACUGCUCUCAUGCUGGCCUGUGAGAUUGGCAGCUCUAACGCUGUGGAAGCCUUAAUUAAAAAGGGUGCAGACCUAAACCUUGUAGAUUCUCUUGGAUACAAUGCCUUACAUUAUUCCAAACUCUCAGAAAAUGCAGGAAUUCAAAGCCUUCUAUUAUCAAAAAUCUCUCAGGAUGCUGAUUUAAAGACCCCAACAAAACCAAAGCAGCAUGACCAAGUCUCUAAAAUAAGCUCAGAAAGAAGUGGAACUCCAAAAAAACGCAAAGCUCCACCACCUCCUAUCAGUCCUACCCAGUUGAGUGAUGUCUCUUCCCCAAGAUCAAUAACUUCGACUCCACUAUCGGGAAAGGAAUCGGUAUUUUUUGCUGAACCACCCUUCAAGGCUGAGAUCAGUUCUAUACGAGAAAACAAAGACAGACUAAGUGACAGUACUACAGGUGCUGAUAGCUUAUUGGAUAUAAGUUCUGAAGCUGACCAACAAGAUCUUCUCUCUCUAUUGCAAGCAAAAGUUGCUUCCCUUACCUUACACAAUAAGGAGUUACAAGAUAAAUUACAGGCCAAAUCACCCAAGGAGGCGGAAGCAGACCUAAGCUUUGACUCAUACCAUUCCACCCAAACUGACUUGGGCCCAUCCCUGGGAAAACCUGGUGAAACCUCUCCCCCAGACUCCAAAUCAUCUCCAUCUGUCUUAAUACAUUCUUUAGGUAAAUCCACUACUGACAAUGAUGUCAGAAUUCAGCAACUGCAAGAGAUUUUGCAAGAUCUACAGAAGAGAUUAGAGAGCUCUGAAGCAGAGAGAAAACAGCUACAGGUCGAACUCCAAUCCCGAAGGGCAGAACUGGUAUGCUUAAACAACACUGAGAUUUCAGAGAACAGCUCUGACCUCAGCCAGAAACUUAAAGAAACUCAGAGCAAAUACGAGGAGGCUAUGAAAGAAGUCCUUAGUGUGCAGAAGCAGAUGAAACUCGGUCUUGUCUCACCUGAAAGCAUGGAUAAUUAUUCACAUUUCCACGAGCUGAGGGUCACGGAAGAGGAAAUAAAUGUGCUAAAGCAGGAUCUGCAGAAUGCAUUAGAAGAAAGUGAAAGAAAUAAAGAGAAAGUGAGAGAGUUAGAGGAAAAACUGGUAGAGAGGGAGAAAGGUACAGUGAUUAAGCCACCUGUGGAAGAGUACGAGGAAAUGAAAAGUUCAUAUUGCUCUGUUAUUGAGAAUAUGAAUAAGGAGAAAGCAUUUUUGUUUGAGAAAUACCAAGAAGCCCAAGAAGAAAUCAUGAAAUUAAAAGACACACUAAAAAGUCAGAUGACACAGGAAGCCAGUGAUGAAGCUGAGGACAUGAAAGAAGCCAUGAAUAGGAUGAUAGAUGAACUCAAUAAACAGGUGAGCGAGCUGUCACAGCUGUACAAAGAAGCCCAGGCUGAGCUGGAGGAUUACAGGAAGAGGAAAUCUCUAGAGGAUGUCACAGCUGAAUAUAUCCAUAAAGCAGAGCAUGAGAAACUGAUGCAAUUGACAAACGUGUCCAGGGCUAAAGCAGAAGAUGCACUGUCUGAAAUGAAGUCUCAGUAUUCAAAAGUGUUGAAUGAGUUGACCCAGCUCAAACAACUGGUGGAUGCACAAAAAGAGAACUCUGUCUCUAUCACAGAACAUUUGCAAGUGAUAACCACGCUGCGGACUGCAGCAAAAGAGAUGGAAGAAAAAAUAAGCAAUCUUAAGGAACACCUUGCAAGCAAGGAAGUGGAAGUAGCAAAGCUGGAGAAACAACUCUUAGAAGAGAAAGCUGCUAUGACUGAUGCAAUGGUACCUCGGUCUUCCUAUGAAAAACUCCAGUCAUCCUUAGAGAGUGAAGUGAGUGUGUUGGCAUCGAAAUUAAAGGAAUCUGUGAAAGAGAAAGAGAAGGUCCAUUCAGAGGUUGUCCAGAUUAGAAGUGAGGUCUCACAGGUGAAAAGAGAAAAGGAAAAUAUUCAGACUCUCUUGAAAUCCAAAGAGCAAGAAGUAAAUGAACUUCUGCAAAAAUUCCAGCAAGCUCAGGAAGAACUUGCAGAAAUGAAAAGAUACGCUGAGAGCUCUUCAAAACUGGAGGAAGAUAAAGAUAAAAAGAUAAAUGAGAUGUCGAAGGAAGUCACCAAAUUGAAGGAGGCCUUGAACAGCCUCUCCCAGCUCUCCUACUCAACAAGCUCAUCCAAAAGGCAGAGUCAGCAGCUGGAGGCGCUGCAGCAGCAAGUCAAACAGCUCCAGAACCAGCUGGCGGAAUGCAAGAAACAACACCAGGAGGUCAUAUCAGUUUACAGAAUGCAUCUUCUGUAUGCUGUGCAGGGCCAGAUGGAUGAAGAUGUCCAGAAAGUACUGAAGCAAAUCCUUACCAUGUGUAAAAACCAGUCUCAAAAGAAGUAAAGUGGAUUCCUUGGCAGGACACUGCCCCUUGUCAUCUGUCUUUGUGUUAGAUCCAGAGUUGUCGGCAGCCGCUGCCAUUGUUCUCAUUCGUGGUAUGCACUGUGGCCUAGCGUAGCUUCUUCCCUUUCCAAAGGUUUCUGAGGACUUCUCCCAGGAGAAGACUGCCCGCCUCAGAACUGCUUAGAGACUUCAAACCAGCAGAGGUGAAAGUCCCUGUCAUCCCUUCAGAUUCCAGAGCUGGGAUCAGCCAUGCCCAGAGGUCUGGUCCUGAUGCUGGCAGGGGGGCCCCCUCCUCCAUCCCUGACUGGCUGAGUGGCUUUAUCACCACCGAGUGAUGUGCUGAGGCCUCCUGCAGUGAAUGCUCCUUCCAUUCCUGUACUCGGGCAGUGCCAUUCAGCACAGGAGAGCUCUUUUUGCCUUUGGCUUUCAAUUCCAAAACAUGAUUUAAUUUCUAACUAAAUUAGUAUGGCACUAGUUAUGAAGUAUCUGCUUAAAACCCUUCAUCAUGAUAUCCUGUGGAUUUAAAAACUCUAAUUCCAUGUUUUCUUCCCAUCUGCCUUAUAUAUCUCAUCACCCUGCUUAUCAAUAUUCAGUUUGAUGAGCACUAUUAACUAAAAUAUGAAACUUAAAAACAAAAGCAAGUUGUCCUUAAAAGUUCUUUUUUUAAGUAAAUUGUUGACAUACUGCAAAUUUUCUAUGCAAACUUGCCUCCUGCUGUUAUCUGUGAAGCUCAGGAAAUCCAAACAUUUGUGUUUCAACAAGGGACAGUAAACUGUGUGUUUACAGCCAAAAGAAAUGCCUCAUAGUUCUUAACCUCAACUUUUGUAGAAGUAUUUUUUUCUCUGUAAUAUUUUUAUUGGCUCAUAAAGAUGUUUUCAUAUCUGAACUCCUAAAUAAGUGAAAUUACAGUAGAUUAUAUUAACAAAAUACUUUUUAGGUAGCCAUGCUUGAGACUUUUUAAAAAUAUAACUUUUUCCUUAAAGUUUUCAGCUAUAGCAAAAGGUAGUUAUGUAUGCCAGACCUAAUAUGAGCUGCCACCAACACCCCUAGAACUUUCAGCCAUGGUGUCUUCAGAAUUGUAGCGCAUUUCUGAAUCUAGCAAAUCCUCCUUUUACCCGUUGAAUGUUUUGAAUGCCCUGACUCUACCAGCGCCCAUAAAUGAUCUCUAGAAGGACUGUUAGUACCAAUCUGUUUUUCAACUUUGAAGCUAAAAACCCUGAUAUGGUAAUAUUAUGGUGCAUAGCAGAGGUCUCGGAAAAAAAAUAUUUCUGUUCACUUUACUUUCAGGUUAAAAAUGUUUCUAACACGCUUGCAACUUCCCUUAUGGCAUUAAUCUUGUUGAGGGAGAGAGACAGAAUCCUGGACUCUCCAAAGUAUUUAACUGAAAGUAGGGCCUGCUCUGACAGGGCCCAUGUCCCACAAGGCUGCUUGGCCUCAGUGGGUGCUUGGCUGUGCUGGAUGAUAUGUUGAUCUGUAUUGGAUAAGGACCAAUGACAGCAAAGCAAAAAUGGCUUUAAAGCUUGGUGUUACUUUUCUUAAGUUGUUUAAUUAUAGUUAAGCAAUUUCAAAAAUGCUCCAAAGAAAUGUGAAAGGACCUUUUGUCACAGCACUUCAGAAAAUACACAACAGCCCCUUCUGCCCCCGCACAGAAAUGCUGCAGAGUAUAUAAAACUUGAGACAUUUUUGUAGGAUGCCUGACGAGGUGUAGCCUUUUAUCUUGUUUCCGGAUGCAUAUUUAUUACGAGUACUCUGGUUAAAUAUUGAAAAGUUAUAUGCUGUAGUUUUUAGUAUUUUGUCUUUGUAAUUUACAGAAGUUAUUGGAGAAAAUAAACUUGUUUCAUUUUGCA